GGGGCCGCUGGCCGAGAGGCUGAGGCGGCGUCAUGUCCUCCGAGGUGUCCGCGCGCCGCGACGCCAAGAAGCUGGUGCGCUCCCCGAGCGGCCUGCGCAUGGUGCCCGAACACCGCGCCUUCGGAAGCCCGUUCGGCCUGGAGGAGCCGCAGUGGGUCCCGGACAAGGAGUGUCGGAGAUGUAUGCAGUGUGACGCCAAGUUUGACUUUCUCACCAGAAAGCACCACUGUCGCCGCUGCGGGAAGUGCUUCUGCGACAGGUGCUGCAGCCAGAAGGUGCCGCUGCGGCGCAUGUGCUUUGUGGACCCCGUGCGGCAGUGCGCGGAGUGCGCCCUCGUGUCCCUCAAGGAGGCGGAGUUCUACGACAAGCAGCUCAAAGUGCUCCUGAGCGGAGCCACCUUCCUCGUCACGUUUGGAAACUCAGAGAAACCUGAAACUAUGACUUGUCGUCUUUCCAAUAACCAGAGAUACUUGUUUCUGGAUGGAGACAGCCACUAUGAAAUCGAAAUUGUACACAUUUCCACCGUGCAGAUCCUCACAGAAGGCUUCCCUCCUGGAGAAAAAGACAUUCACGCUUACACCAGCCUCCGGGGGAGCCAGCCUGCCUCUGAAGGAGGCAACGCACGGGCCACAGGCAUGUUCCUGCAGUAUACAGUGCCGGGGACGGAGGGUGUGACCCAGCUGAAGCUGACAGUGGUGGAGGACGUGACUGUGGGCAGGAGGCAGGCGGUGGCGUGGCUAGUGGCCAUGCACAAGGCUGCCAAGCUCCUCUAUGAAUCUCGGGACCAGUAACUCUACGUGGGGCUGAGCUUGGAGUACGUGUGGUCACCAGGACUGAGUCGCUUGGAACAGCAGAGCCUGCUCCUUGCGUACCACAGGGAUUAAUCCUGCUUGUGCUGGGAAAUGCAACUCACUCAUGUAUUUGGAGAAACAGGAGUGUUCACUUAUCUAGUGCAAUAUGUUCACAGUUUAUUAAUGCUUUAAACAGCUUCAUGUUUUAGAAUUUGUGUAUUGUCAAUACUUAAUUGGGGGUGGGAGAGACUGAGCUACACUACUGCUAAACUAUUUUUAGCAUAAUAUAUACCAUUUUUAUGAGUUCGCAGGUCUACUAGAAGGUUCUGGCCCAUCAAUAUUCAUUUCAUUUAAUUCUUCCACAGAACCAGUUUGGGCAGUAGGAACUCAGGCUUCUGGUCUGCAGUGGAGCCUGUUCGCCUCUAAUAGCCAGUUUACAGCACUUGCCUUAGCCUGUUUCACAGACUUGUCCACUUACCUUGUCACUAAUUUGGGGCUUCUGGGCUGUGAGUGAUCCUUUGAUACUUCACCAAGGGGAACGUGGGGGCUUUGUGUUUUGUACUUUUCACUCACUAUUUCACUUUAUUAAGAUGACUGUACAGCAAUUUGUAUAUAAAGCUUAUGAUUAAAAACUAUUUUGAACAUA